AAGCUGAGAGGGCCCGCGGGUAGGCAUGGCGGCGCACCUUAAGAAGCGGGUUUAUGAGGAAUUCACGAAAGUGGUUCAGCCACAGGAGGAAAUUGCUACUAAGAAACUCCGACUAACAAAACCAAGUAAAUCUGCAGCACUCCACAUAGAUCUGUGUAAAGCUACCUCCCCAGCAGAUGCUUUGCAAUACUUGCUCCAGUUUGCCAGGAAGCCUGUCGAGGCGGAAAGCGUAGAGGGAGUAGUCAGGAUUCUCUUGGAACAUUAUUACAAGGAGAAUGAUCCAUCUGUGAGACUGAAAAUUGCAUCAUUGUUGGGUUUAUUAUCAAAGACAGCAGGAUUUUCACCAGACUGCAUUAUGGAUGAUGCCAUCAACAUCCUGCAGAAUGAAAAGUCUCAUCAAGUCCUAGCUCAACUGCUGGAUACUUUGCUUGCAAUUGGCACUAAGCUACCAGAGAAUCAAGCUAUCCAAAUGCGAUUAGUUGAUGUGGCCUGCAAGCAUCUGACAGAUACGUCUCAUGGUGUAAGAAAUAAGUGCCUGCAGUUACUUGGCAAUCUUGGCUCUUUGGAGAAAAGUGUCACAAAAGAUGCAGAAGGCCUAGCUGCCAGAGAUGUCCAGAAGAUUAUAGGGGAUUACUUCAGUGACCAAGACCCACGUGUCAGAACAGCAGCUAUAAAAGCCAUGUUGCAGCUCCAUGAAAGAGGACUGAAAUUACACCAAACAAUUUAUAAUCAGGCCUGUAAAUUACUCUCUGAUGACUAUGAACAAGUGCGCAGUGCUGCAGUCCAGCUUAUCUGGGUCGUCAGUCAGCUCUAUCCUGAAAGCAUUGUCCCAAUUCCUUCUUCUAAUGAAGAAAUACGCUUAGUUGAUGAUGCGUUUGGCAAAAUUUGUCACAUGGUCAGUGAUGGCUCUUGGGUGGUUCGUGUUCAGGCAGCAAAACUGUUGGGCUCUAUGGAGCAAGUCAGUUCUCAUUUCUUGGAGCAGACCCUUGACAAGAAGCUGAUGUCAGAUCUGAGGAGGAAACGUACUGCACAUGAGCGUGCCAAGGAACUUUACAGUUCGGGGGAGUUUUCCAGUGGCAGAAAGUGGGGAGAUGAUGCUCCCAAGGAAGAAGUAGAUACCGGGGCUGUGAACUUGAUUGAGUCAGGAGCUUGUGGAGCUUUUGUUCAUGGGUUGGAAGAUGAGAUGUAUGAGGUUCGUAUUGCUGCUGUGGAGGCCCUCUGCAUGUUGGCCCAGUCUUCACCCUCUUUUGCUGAGAAGUGCCUUGAUUUCCUAGUUGACAUGUUCAACGAUGAAAUUGAGGAAGUACGUCUGCAGUCUAUACAUACCAUGAGAAAAAUCUCUAACAACAUCACCCUCCGAGAAGAUCAGCUUGACACUGUCCUGGCUGUGCUAGAGGAUUCAUCCAGAGAUAUUCGAGAGGCUCUUCAUGAACUCUUAUGCUGUACUAAUGUUUCAACCAAAGAAGGGAUUCAUCUUGCAUUGGUGGAGCUGCUGAAAAAUUUAACCAAGUACCCUACUGAUAGGGACUCCAUAUGGAAGUGCUUGAAGUUUCUGGGAAGUCGGCAUCCAACCCUGGUGCUUCCCUUGGUGCCAGAGCUUCUGAGCACCCACCCAUUUUUUGACACAGCUGAACCAGACAUGGAUGAUCCAGCUUAUAUUGCAGUUUUGGUACUUAUUUUCAAUGCUGCUAAAACCUGUCCAACAAUGCCAGCAUUGUUCUCAGAUCACACCUUCAGGCACUAUGCCUACCUCCGAGACAGUCUUUCUCAUCUUGUUCCUGCCUUGAGGUUACCAGGUAGAAAACUGGUGUCAUCAGCUGUUUCUCCCAGCAUCAUACCUCAAGAGGAUCCUUCCCAGCAGUUCCUGCAGCAGAGCCUUGAAAGAGUGUAUAGUCUUCAGCACUUGGACCCUCAGGGAGCCCAGGAGCUGCUGGAAUUCACCAUCAGGGAUCUGCAAAGACUUGGAGAACUUCAAUCUGAAUUGGCAGGAGUAGCUGAUUUCUCUGCCACCUAUCUUCGCUGUCAACUACUUCUCAUCAAGGCCUUGCAGGAAAAGUUGUGGAAUGUAGCUGCCCCUUUGUAUUUGAAGCAGAGUGAUUUGGCCUCAGCAGCAGCGAAACAGAUUAUGGAAGAGACCUACAAAAUGGAAUUCAUGUACAGUGGUGUGGAGAAUAAGCAGGUGGUGAUUAUACAUCACAUGAGGCUGCAGGCCAAAGCUUUGCAACUUAUAGUAACAGCACGAACUACACGAGGACUUGACCCCUUAUUUGGGAUGUGUGAAAAAUUUUUACAGGAAGUAGACUUUUUUCAGAGGUAUUUCAUCGCUGAUUUGCCCCACUUGCAGGACAGCUUUGUGGACAAACUCCUUGACCUUAUGCCCCGACUCAUGACAUCCAAACCUGCAGAAGUGGUCAAAAUUCUACAGACCAUGCUGCGACAGAGUGCCUUUCUGCAUCUCCCGCUUCCAGAGCAGAUCCACAAAGCCUCAGCCACCAUCAUCGAGCCAGCGGGCGAGUCAGACAACCCUUUGCGGUUUACCUCUGGGUUGGUGGUUGCCCUGGAUGUUGAUGCAACCCUGGAGCAUGUGCAGGAUCCUCAGAACACUGUUAAGGUCCAGGUCUUAUAUCCAGAUGGCCAGGCUCAGAUGAUUCACCCCAAGCCUGCAGACUUCCGGAAUCCUGGCCCAGGGCGGCACCGGCUCAUCACUCAGGUUUAUCUCUCCCACACCGCUUGGACAGGAUGUGCCAUGAAGCUGUAGCCAGGUGGAAUUGUACCACAGCCCUGACAUGAACACCUGAUGGCAGCUGCUGGGUUGGAGCCUAGACAAAAACAUGAAGAACCAUGGCUGCUGCCUGAGCCCAUCGUGCUGUAAUUAUAGAAAACCUUCUAAGGGAAGAAUAUGCUGAUAUUUUUCAGAUAAGUACCCCUUUUAUAAAAAUCCUCCAAGUUAGCCCUCAUUUUCCAUGUAAGGAAACAGAGGCUUUGAGAUAAUGUCUGUCUCCUAAGGGACAAAGCCAGGACUUGAUCCUGUCUUAAAAAUGCAAAAUGUAGUACUUCUUCCAUCAAAGGUAGACAUGCACUAAGGGACAGGUUUUGGCUUGGUAUCAGAAUACAUUUUUAAAAGCUGUGUAAGAAUUGAACGGGCUGUACUAGGGGGUAUAGAAUUCUCCAGGCUAGAUGAGUUUGGGCAGAGGUUGAACAAGCUCCUGACAAAUUUGUUGCUAAGCAAUUCAAGUAUCGUAUCGGGGUUGGGCUCAACUUUUUAAAUUGCUUUUACCCUGAAUUUUCACGUUCUGGGGAACAUGAGAAUUUUAGUUUUUCUCUAUCUGAUUCUGUACUUUUUCACUGAAGUGAAAAAAAAAAAAAGACCUUUUUAUAAAGGUUUCGAAGGGGGCAUAAAGAGCACUCCAGUGUGGCACCUUCAUUUACAAAUGAAUACGCAGGCCCAGAGAGACUGAGUUAGUGGUGAAGCUAAGCCUGGAACCCAGGCCUCUGGUUUCUUCCCCAGGUGACUUUCAUCACAGGGGUCUGUUCUUAGUGAGUGGUCUAGCAUGCACCCAGCAGUCAGAGCCAGAAACCUGUUUGGCACGUUGGAUUCCUUCCUCAUCCCUCAUACAAAAGUAGCCAUCAAGUCCUUUAGAUUCCUCUUCCUUCAUGUUUCUUAGUCCUCUUCUUAUACUGUUUGUAUACUGAUGGAACCACCAUCAGCCCUCCUUAAGUGAUGAGCUGAUCUGACCACACCAUUCCCCUGCUCAGUCCCUUUCAGUGGAUCACUGCUCAUCCCAGGAAAAAGUCUGAACUCCUGUCUUGAAGGCUCUUCAUGGCUCUGCUUCGUUUCCAGCCUCAUACUCCCUGUCCCAAACUGUCUCUGUACUCCACUUGAACAGAAUUACCUGUAGUCUUUUUCUGUCACCUCUAGGCCUUUGGACCUGCUGAGCCUGGGAAUGUGCUCCUCAGACUGUCUCCUGUGGUUCUUUCCUUCCAUUCUUCAGGACUGGGCCUUGUUCUAGGACAUAUCUGUGUCUCUUAUGGGCUUGGAACAUUUCCUCUAUGUUCCCACAGCCUCCUAUACUAUAUUCUUCACACAUAGUAUAGUAUUUAUUAAUAUGGCAUUGCAGGUUCACAAAUGCAAACCCCUUAAGAAAGGUAGGCAGGAAAAGUAAAGGAAUAAAGUGGCCUAGAAGAUAACAGCAAUUGGAAGAAUCAGAGAGCACAUUCUCUGUUGGAGAAGGCGGUGCUAUUCCAUUCCACUCAGUUAUUUUCAUUUAUAAGUGUGGACCUAGUGGUGUCAGUUCUUCCCAUUCUUCCAAAACAGCCAGAAAUCUUCAUUUUCAUGAAAGUUAAAAAACCUUGGUAACUACAGUAAAUAUUAAAAUUACUGAGACAAACAAAACAUGUCUCCAGGCAGAUUUGUGCCAAUUUGCAACUUCUACAUCCUCACUGUAAUGUUUACACGCCUUAUUUCUUCCAACUGAUCUGUACCUGGACUGUAAGAAUGUCUGUGCUGUAUGCCCAGCACAACUCCUGGCACAUAACCGGGCAAGGAAAGAAUGAUUCUAUGUCUCCAGAGCAAAGGUAGCAGUACCAUGGCAUGCUGCAAAAAAAGAUUCAGGUUUCUGAAAGGACUUUAUAUUUGCUUUGAGAUGAUUGAACUCAGCAAACACAAUCAUGGAGAAGAAAGGUACACACCUAGCUGUGGCCAGCUUCAUGUCUUUUUUUUUUUUUUUGAGAUGGAGUCUUGCUCUGUCACCCAGGCUGGAGUGCAGUGGCACGAUCUCACCUCACAGCAGGCUCUGCCGCCCUGGUUCCAGCGAUUCUCCUGCCUCAGCCUCCCAAGUAGACUAGCUGGGAUUACAGGCACGUGCCACCACGCCUGGCUAAUUUUUGUAUUUUUAGUAGAGAUGGGGUUUCACCAUGUUGGCCAGGCUGGUCUCGAACUGCUGACCUCAGGUGAUCUGCCCACCUCGGCCUCCCAAAGCGCUGGGAUUACAGGCGUGAGCCACCGCACCCGGCCAACUUCUUGUCUUAACCACUCAGGCUAGAAGAAAUGACCUGUGGGCAGCUUGAGGGCUGUUCUACCUACAAACUAACUCAGAGGCUUUAAUGAUUUAAGACAGAGGACUAAGUAUAGUUAUGUGGAGAAACAGCUUCCCUUCAAGCUCUACAUAUUUCCAUCGUUAACCAUGUGCACCAGGUUCCAAAGUAGGGGCUAUGUAUUAGCAGGUUUUCUUAAAAGUUUAAUAAUGUCACUGACAGAUACUUCUGUCUCUAAGAAGUUUACACUAAGUUCUCUUUAAUUGGAGACAACUCACUUAGGAAGAAUGAUUACACCCACACUGAAUUCAACACCCACCAGAGCUGUCUCACCUUACAUUUGACCAAAAAAAAAAAAAAAAGACUGCAUCAC